AAACGACCCGGUGGGUCUACAGCGGAAGGGAGGGAGCGAAGGUAGGAGGCAGGGCUUGCCUCACUGGCCACCCUCCCAACCCCAAGAGCCCAGCCCCAUGGUCCCCGCCGCCGGCGCGCUGCUGUGGGUCCUGCUGCUGAAUCUGGGUCCCCGGGCGGCGGGGGCCCAAGGCCUGACCCAGACUCCGACCGAAAUGCAGCGGGUCAGUUUACGCUUUGGGGGCCCCAUGACCCGCAGCUACCGGAGCACCGCCCGGACUGGUCUUCCCCGGAAGACAAGGAUAAUCCUAGAGGACGAGAAUGAUGCCAUGGCCGACGCCGACCGCCUGGCUGGACCAGCGGCUGCCGAGCUCUUGGCCGCCACGGUGUCCACCGGCUUUAGCCGGUCGUCCGCCAUUAACGAGGAGGAUGGGUCUUCAGAAGAGGGGGUUGUGAUUAAUGCCGGAAAGGAUAGCACCAGCAGAGAGCUUCCCAGUGCGACUCCCAAUACAGCGGGGAGUUCCAGCACGAGGUUUAUAGCCAAUAGUCAGGAGCCUGAAAUCAGGCUGACUUCAAGCCUGCCGCGCUCCCCCGGGAGGUCUACUGAGGACCUGCCAGGCUCGCAGGCCACCCUGAGCCAGUGGUCCACACCUGGGUCUACCCCGAGCCGGUGGCCGUCACCCUCACCCACAGCCAUGCCAUCUCCUGAGGAUCUGCGGCUGGUGCUGAUGCCCUGGGGCCCGUGGCACUGCCACUGCAAGUCGGGCACCAUGAGCCGGAGCCGGUCUGGGAAGCUGCACGGCCUUUCCGGGCGCCUUCGAGUUGGGGCGCUGAGCCAGCUCCGCACGGAGCACAAGCCUUGCACCUAUCAACAAUGUCCCUGCAACCGACUUCGGGAAGAGUGCCCCCUGGACACAAGUCUCUGUACUGACACCAACUGUGCCUCUCAGAGCACCACCAGUACCAGGACCACCACUACCCCCUUCCCCACCAUCCACCUCAGAAGCAGUCCCAGCCUGCCACCCGCCAGCCCCUGCCCAGCCCUGGCUUUUUGGAAACGGGUCAGGAUUGGCCUGGAGGAUAUUUGGAAUAGCCUCUCUUCAGUGUUCACAGAGAUGCAACCAAUAGACAGAAACCAGAGGUAAUGGCCACUUCAUCCACAUGAGGAGAUGUCAGUAUCUCAACCUCUCUUGCCCUUUCAAUCCUAGCACCCACUAGAUAUUUUUAGUACAGAAAAACAAAACUGGAAAACACAUUGUUUGGUCUUGUGUUUCUUUACAGAGGUACCUGAGGGAGGAGAGACAUAAAUCCCUUCAUCCCUAAGACUGAACUAUGUAACUAGCAGCCUCUGGCUUGUUUUCUACUCCCUGUCCCUCAGGAUAAAAUGUUGAUAUUGCUCAUUUUCCUCAUUUCCAACAUUGUUUUAAAACAAGUACUUCUUUUACAGGCUUGAAAAAUCUCAAAUAAACGCUAAGAAAAGGGAGUAGGAAGAACAAGGAGUUGAGCCCUUGAAAGAUGACAGUGGUCUUCUUGCCUUCAUGCUUGGCCCUCUCUCCUCAAAAGGGCAAUGUUGGUACAAAAUUCCAUCUCAGCCACUUUCGAGGAGUUAUCUUCAUUAGCUAUAUCCAUCCUUUAAUCCAACACACACCUGCAAUGAUUACUGUGCAACUAUUUUGCUUAAUUUUUUAUUUGAAAAAAUGUAUUUAAAAGUCCAACAACUUUUUAAUAUAAAUUACGACUCUCAAACCCAUUCCCAUCACUUUAUUAGUGAUGGUAGCAUACAUAUUAGAGAAGGUAGCUAAAGGCAAGAGAGCACCAAAGGAAAAAGACUGUCCAAAGAACAGGUAUUAGAAUGAGGCCGAAGAUCACGGUGACCAGAGAUUUCUAGGAGUCUCUAACCUUUCCACCCUAUCCUGUUAACCCUUUAGAUCUCUAGUAUAACACUCAGGCUACUGAGGUAUUUUAGAGCAACAAGCUGGGUUACUUUCAGAGCAACCAGCUUGACUGGAACUGAGAGUAAAUUGGGAAUGUAUGACCAAUCUUAGACCCUGAAAAAUGGCAGAAAAUACAUGGAAAUUUGAAAAAAAAAAAAAAAAAAAAAAAAAAA